AGUGUCUUCCACUCGGUGCGUCUCUCUAGGAGCCGCGCGGGAAGGAUGCUGGUCCGCAGGGGCGCGCGCGCAGGGCCCAGGAUGCCGCGGGGCUGGACCGCGCUUUGCUUGCUGAGUUUGCUGCCUUCUGGGUUCAUGAGUCUUGACAACAACGGUACUGCUACCCCAGAGUUACCUACCCAGGGAACAUUUUCAAAUGUUUCUACAAAUGUAUCCUACCAAGAAACUACAACACCUAGUACCCUUGGAAGUACCAGCCUGCACCCUGUGUCUCAACAUGGCAAUGAGGCCACAACAAACAUCACAGAAACGACAGUCAAAUUCACAUCUACCUCUGUGAUAACCUCAGUUUAUGGAAACACAAACUCUUCUGUCCAGUCACAGACCUCUGUAAUCAGCACAGUGUUCACCACCCCAGCCAACGUUUCAACUCCAGAGACAACCUUGAAGCCUAGCCUGUCACCUGGAAAUGUUUCAGACCUUUCAACCACUAGCACUAGCCUUGCAACAUCUCCCACUAAACCCUAUACAUCAUCUUCUCCUAUCCUAAGUGACAUCAAGGCAGAAAUCAAAUGUUCAGGCAUCAGAGAAGUGAAAUUGACUCAGGGCAUCUGCCUGGAGCAAAAUAAGACCUCCAGCUGUGCGGAGUUUAAGAAGGACAGGGGAGAGGGCCUGGCCCGAGUGCUGUGUGGGGAGGAGCAGGCUGAUGCUGAUGCUGGGGCCCAGGUAUGCUCCCUGCUCCUUGCCCAGUCUGAGGUGAGGCCUCAGUGUCUACUGCUGGUCUUGGCCAACAGAACAGAAAUUUCCAGCAAACUCCAACUUAUGAAAAAGCACCAAUCUGACCUGAAAAAGCUGGGGAUCCUAGAUUUCACUGAGCAAGAUGUUGCAAGCCACCAGAGCUAUUCCCAAAAGACCCUGAUUGCACUGGUCACCUCGGGAGCCCUGCUGGCUGUCUUGGGCAUCACUGGCUAUUUCCUGAUGAAUCGCCGCAGCUGGAGCCCCACAGGAGAAAGGCUGGGCGAAGACCCUUAUUACACGGAAAACGGUGGAGGCCAGGGCUAUAGCUCAGGACCUGGGACCUCCCCUGAGGCUCAGGGAAAGGCCAGUGUGAACCGAGGGGCUCAGGAAAACGGGACCGGCCAGGCCACCUCCAGAAACGGCCAUUCAGCAAGACAACACGUGGUGGCUGAUACCGAAUUGUGACUCGGCUAGGUGGGGCAAGGCUGGGCAGUGUCCGAGAGAGCACCCCUCUCUGCAUCUGACCACGUGCUACCCCCAUGCUGGAGGUGACAUCUCUUACGCCCAACCCUUCCCCACUGCACACACCUCAGAGGCUGUUCUUGGGGCCCUACACCUUGAGGAGGGGCAGGUAAACUCCUGUCCUUUACACAUUCGGCUCCCUGGAGCCAGACUCUGGUCUUCUUUGGGUAAACGUGUGACGGGGGAAAGCCAAGGUCUGGAGAAGCUCCCAGGAACAAUCGAUGGCCUUGCAGCACUCACACAGGACCCCCUUCCCCUACCCCCUCCUCUCUGCCGCAAUACAGGAACCCCCAGGGGAAAGAUGAGCUUUUCUAGGCUACAAUUUUCUCCCAGGAAGCUUUGAUUUUUACCGUUUCUUCCCUGUAUUUUCUUUCUCUACUUUGAGGAAACCAAAGUAACCUUUUGCACCUGCUCUCUUGUAAUGAUAUAGCCAGAAAAACGUGUUGCCUUGAACCACUUCCCUCAUCUCUCCUCCAAGACACUGUGGACUUGGUCACCAGCUCCUCCCUUGUUCUCUAAGUUCCACUGAGCUCCAUGUGCCCCCUCUACCAUUUGCAGAGUCCUGCACAGUUUUCUGGCUGGAGCCUAGAACAGGCCUCCCAAGUUUUAGGACAAACAGCUCAGUUCUAGUCUCUCUGGGGCCACACAGAAACUCUUUUUGGGCUCCUUUUUCUCCCUCUGGAUCAAAGUAGGCAGGACCAUGGGACCAGGUCUUGGAGCUGAGCCUCUCACCUGUACUCUUCCGAAAAAUCCUCUUCCUCUGAGGCUGGAUCCUAGCCUUAUCCUCUGAUCUCCAUGGCUUCCUCCUCCCUCCUGCCGACUCCUGGGUUGAGCUGUUGCCUCAGUCCCCCAACAGAUGCUUUUCUGUCUCUGCCUCCCUCACCCUGAGCCCCUUCCUUGCUCUGCACCCCCAUAUGGUCAUAGCCCAGAUCAGCUCCUAACCCUUAUCACCAGCUGCCUCUUCUGUGGGUGACCCAGGUCCUUGUUUGCUGUUGAUUUCUUUCCAGAGGGGUUGAGCAGGGAUCCUGGUUUCAAUGACGGUUGGAAAUAGAAAUUUCCAGAGAAGAGAGUAUUGGGUAGAUAUUUUUUCUGAAUACAAAGUGAUGUGUUUAAAUACUGCAAUUAAAGUGAUACUGAAACACAUCUGUUAUGUGACUCUGUCUUAGCUGGGUGUGUCUGCAUGCAAGAGUGACACCCUCCAUUAGACCUAGCUAGACUGUGCAGUGAUGUGGUGGGGAGGACCAGCCAGGGAAGAGGGAGCACCUCAGCAGACACAGGCACCAGCCAGGAUGCUAAGGACCUUUAGCCAAGUCUGCCAACUAUUCUCCUCCAUGGGGAGAGGAAACAUCCAUUUCCAGUGGUAGAAAGGCAGACCCGAAUGUACCAGGGAGCUUCCAAAUGGAGGGUGGUAUGUUGGGUUCUUAGGAGCUGUACCCUUCAUGAACACCCUUCUGAGAAGAGGAGCAUGCUGAUCACUGCUGCAAAAUAUGCAAAACAAAGGGAAGGGGCAAUGUCCUGUGCACCCUUUAUUAUCAGGCCACCCCCCUCCCCAGCCCCCCAGGUCAGAGUAGACACAGUGAAGGACUAUGUGGGGACUGUUGUUCUAGAGACCUGGCAGCCAACUCAGGGAGGGGGCUGGUUUCCACCCUCAAGAUUAAGACAGCAGCCUAAUUAAAAAAAAAAUCUGUAAGCAUGUACCUCCCCCCAGCUUCCAAAACAACCCCCACCCCACCCCUACCAGGCCAUAGGAAGUUGGGGAGGGAGUGCUGAGGAGCUCCAGGAAACACUCCCAAGUGUGUCGACAGUGGCAGAGGCAGUUGGGGCCAAACAAAGGUUGAUUCUUCCAUUCUUAUCUCCAUAAAGCCAGACCUUUCCCUUCAGCACUCCUCCACCCCCAUCUCCUUCUUGCUUUUCUCCAACUCCUCUAAUCAUAGGUUCUUCCCUAGGACAGAGGGGAGGCGAAAUGAUGAGGUUCAGAGUCUUCCCUCAAAGGCGAUGGCUGCCUUGAGGGUUGGAGCAAAGGAUGAUGAGCAAAAGACGAUGGUAAUCAGUAGGGAAGUCCAGCCCACUUGCAUCUAGUUGCACAUCUUGCCUUGAGAGUAAUCCAGUGAGGGUCUGUCCCAGCUAGGACAUCAAGUAGGAGGGGUGGGUUCAGGGUUCAGAUUCCUAGGAAAUAUGGGAGGAGAGGAAAAGGCAACUUGGAUGCACCUCCAGCUUCAGGCCUAGCAACCUGCAAUGCAUCUCACCCUGAGUUUGCUGGAAUGUGUAUGUAUGCUUUGGGAGGAAGGGCUGUGUGUGUAUUGCGGGGUGGGGUGGGGCAGCUGGUUCCCUCUGACAGCUGGACAGCUUGCCCUGAAGAAUUUGCCUGCUUUCUGGAAAAAUCCAACUUUCCCACCGUGGGCCUGAGCGUCCUGGUACAGCAAUGGCGCCACCUGCUGGCCUUAUUGAGGUCCUACUGCUCAGCCUCAGCUCAAUCGCCUCCAUGUUGGGCUUCUCUCCCUGGCUGCCCCACCCUCUAGUCCAAUUUCUCUUGUACACAAAGCUCAUAUAACUAUAGAACGUCACUGUUGAAGAGAACUUUAAAGAUACAUUUAAUUAAACUCCCUUAUGGUAUAGUUAAAGACAAACUAAGGCUCAGAGAAGGGAGGUGGCUUGCCCAAUCACCCAGAAUUCCAAAGUCCUGAAUCUGUAGUUUUCCCUUCCAUCAUAUCAUCCUACUCUUCUGCCGAGUCCUCCGUGUUACUCCAGUUGGAUGUCAUGAAGCCAGUGUGGCAGUGUGAAGAUAGGUUUGGGACUUCACUUCUGGAGCAUUUCAUCAACAUAAGCUAUCCUAGGCCUGGCCAGCCAAGCAGGUCCUGGAGGAGCCCCAGGACAAAGAUCACAGGAGGCCAUGAGGUUCGGCUUCUUCGGCGCCCACAGUGAGCCCAGGAAAAUUAGCUGUAGGGUAUUACACUGUUGACUAUGGAGAGCAUAUCUGGAAUUAUCUUCAGCCAGAUUUUCAUCUGAAUGGAUAAAUGGGAAUACCAUCUAAGUCCAGAUAAAUAGAUCACUUCCAUCUCAUCCCUUCUAGGUAGAUUAAUCCCACACUUCCUCUUCACACAAAACCAGUAAUAGGUCAUCGAUUUUGUGCAACAGGAUGCUGCUUCUCUUCCUAAAGCCCCCAUCGAAGAGGCUUCCAGCCACCAUUCAAUCAUUCAUCAAGUCUUAUGAUGUGCCAGACACUGCGCGAAAUGUGCCAGAACAUCUGUUAUGUGCCAGACACUGUUCUUGAGACUGGGGAUACAGCAAACACUCAUGAAGCUUAUAAUUCUAGCAGAAGAGGACAGUAAACAAUGUCAUCUCAGUAAGUAUAUACAUGUGUUUUCAGGAUUGAGAGCUAUGAAAAACAUAAAAUAUAUUGAGAAUAAUGGUUGGUAUUUUACAUAUGGUGGUUACUUUUAGAAAAAUAACAGUGGAGAGCACAGCUUCACUUGAAUGAAGUGGAGAAGCAGGUUGUAUGCCAAGCUGGGAGAGAUUAUCCCACACAGGGGAAAGGACAAGUGCAAAGCCCUAUGAUGAAAAGCUGCCAAGUGCAGAAAGCCUCAGAUGGCAGGGGGCAAGAUGGCCAUGAGGUUGUGUCAGUGAGUGGGGGUGGGGAGAGGCAGGAGGUCAGACUACAUGGGGCCUUUUUAGUUGUAGAUUGGGAAGCCACUGGAGGGUUUUGAGCAGAGAAGUCAUAUCAUCUGCUUUAUGUUUUAAAAGGAUCAUGCUGGCUGCUGAGUAGAGAAUAGAGGUUGAGGGAUAAGAAAGUAGAAGGAGACCGUAGCAAGAAGAACGAUCAUGGCUGGGAGCAGGUGAUCAUAUUGGCAGUGAUGAGAUCAAGCAGAAUUCAAAAAGUGGUUUCAAAGUAGAGGUAACAGGACUUGCUCAGUCUAUUUAUUUCUUCAAAUAAUAAUCAUAUUUACAAUGAUAGUAGCUAACAGUUUUUGAGUGCUUACUGUAUGAAAAUUGAGAUAUGGUGCCAAUAUUUAAAUAGCAUAUUUUACUUAACAUUCACAGAAACCCUGUGAAGUAGGUUCUAUUAUCUCAGAAAAAGAAACUGAAACUCAGAGAAUAACAAGGGACUGUGUUACGUGCACAGUGGCAGAGGCAAAGAUGAAUAGGAUGUGAGUUUAUUUGAACCCCAAAUGUUUAAAUCUUGGGGAUAAUACAACACACAUUUAAACAAAGAAGCAAGAAAAAAAAUGCACAACAGAAAGUGAGAAAUAACACGAGGAAAGACUAAAUGAAGUGCUUUGUAUCUAGAUGUGGGCAGGACCCUUUCCAGCUGAGAAGAUCUGAGACUGGGUCAUGAACAGGUGGUUUCUGAGUGGGUCCUGUAAAAAUGAAUACGAUUUUGAUGAUAGUAAUGAGUAAGGACAUUUGAGACUGAUAGAAGAGUACAUACAAUAUGUAGUGAUGGGGAAAGAUAAGGUACUGUCAAAGGACAAUGUGUUUUCUGGUAUGACAGAGAAGUAGAAUGUGUUAAGGGAAGCCGAGUACCAGAAAGAUCCGGGUGUCACAGUUUGUGUAGGGUGUUUAAAGCUAAACCACAGAGUUUAAUUUUAUCCAAUAGAAGAGGAGCCACAGAAGAGUUUCCAUUUAUUCAUUAAUUUAUUCAUUUAUUCAAAAAAUAUUUGAGUGCUUAUUAUAAGCCAGGUACUAUGCCAGGCACCUGGGAUAAGACAUAGUCCCUUCUGUCAAGUCUUUACAUUGGGUGGAUGUGGGAGGGACAGAUGACAGAACAAUAUGCAUUGAGUGUAAGUGCUAUGGUAUAGGAAGCUCUGAGUGGGAGGGGCAUGGAAGCCGUGGAAGACCAUGGAAGGCUUCCCAGGAGAAGUGACGUCUGGACUGAUCCUUUGGUCAAGCAGGAGUUAAAGAGGAGAAAAGGAGAGAUAUGGGUGUUCCCGAGAGAGGAAGAAGCCUUGUCCCAGGAGCAAAGUGAGGGUGAUUGUUCCAGAAAUGUGAGUGAUUCUUUUAAGGCUCAAGCAAAGCAUGUGAUUCUUCUUUAUACCUUCUAUUUCUUUGCUGAGUGUUUCUGUUCUUUUGUUUCAAGCAUGCUGCAAUUGCUCAUUAAAGCAUGUUUAUGAUGGCUGUCUGUUUUAAAAUUCUUGUCAGAUGGUUUCAACAUCUUUAUCAUCUCAAUGUUGGCAUCUGUUAAUGGUUUUUUCUCAAUCAAAUUGAGAUUUUCCUGGUUCUUGGUAUUACCAGUGAUUUUAAUUGCAUCUGGAAAUUUGGGAUUUAUGUUGAAAGACUGGAUCUUAUUGAAAGAUUCUGUUUAGCACCCCUCCUUUGAUACCACACUGGUGGGUCCAGGUUCCCCAUUCAGCUGUUGACACCUUCAGGGCAGAGAGGUGGGAUGGGGUGAAGGGGGUACCUCAUUAUUGCUGGCCCAGGUUAGAAGUUCAGGCUUCCCAGUAGAUCUCUGCUGAUACCACCCUGGUGCCAUGUCAUUCCUUGAGUCCAAAAGUCCCUCCCAAUUCUGCCUUCUUCUCUCUACAUAUCGGAGUCUCCCUAUGUUUGACUUAUAUAUAAUGUCCAGGGUUUUUAGAGUUAGUUAACAGGAGGCAUAAGAAAAAGUGUGUCCACUCCAUCUUGUCUGGAACUGGAAGUUCAAGUCGAAUAUAAGAGAGAGGAGAGGAAAUUACAAGCCAUGAGACUGGAGAGUUAGGCAGGUUCUACACCAGCUAUUCUCAAAGCCCUCUUACACUCUUAAAAAUUUAGAACUUCAAAGAGCUUUUGAUUUUGAAAGUUACAUCUAUCAAUUAUUACUGUUUCAAAAAUUAAAAUUGAGAAAAUUUUAUUUAUUAAUUUGUUUAAAAAUAACAAUAAUUAUUCAAUUACAUGAUAAUGUAAGUAAUGCUUUUCUUAAUGAAAAAUAAUUAUAUUUUCCAAAACAAAAACAAUUAGGAAAAAGAGUGUCAUUGUUUUAGACUUUGGUAAAUCUCUCUAAUAUCUGGCUGAAGAGAAGAAUGCUGAUUCUUUUUUUUUUUUUUUUUUUUUGAGACGGAGUCUCGCUCUGUCACCCAGGCUGGAGUGUAGUGGUGUGAUCUCGGCUCACUGCAAGCUCUGCCUCCCGGGUUCACGCCAUUCUCCUGCCUCAGCCUCCCAAGUAGCUGGGACUACAGGCACCCGCCACCACGCCCGGCUAAUUUUUUUGUAUUUUUAGUAGAGAUGGGGUUUCACCGUGUUAGCCAGGCUGGUCUCGAUCUCCUGACCUCAUGAUCCACCCACCUCAGCCUCCCAAAGCGCUGGGAUUACAGGUGUGAGACACCGCGCCCAGCCCCCGAAUGCUGAUUCUUUUAUCUGCUUCUGUAUUCAAUCUGUUGUGAUAUGAUGGGUAGCCUCUGAAACACUCCACUGUAUACUUGUGAAAGAAUGAAUGUGAAAAAGGAAAAUAGAUUUGUAGUAUUAUUAUUCAAAUUGUUUUGACCUCAGAGACCACUUGGAAAUGUUUUAGGGAACCCCCAGAGGACCUUGGAUCAUGCUUUGAGAACCGCGGCUCUAGAUAUGUUACUAUUUCAGUAGCAUCUAAGUACAUGUGGCUGCUGAGCACUUGUAAUGUGGCUAGUGCAAAUGAGAGACAGGACUUCCAGCUAUAUGUAAUUUAAUAAACUCAAAUUUAAAAACUGGAACCUCAUAAAAUGUUUUGUUGUUGUUGUUAAACAUGACCUUAUAGUUUUGGUAGGAA